AUGACCACAGCCAGCUGGGGACAAAAGGCCCUUCAUCUUCUGCAGAAGCCUGGAUUGGAGGAGGGCGGCCGCUUCCUUGAGGGCCUGAGUCACAGCCAAGAAGACCCGCUCACUUUUUCCAGAAGUGAGGGAAACUUCCCCGUCAGCCCUGCAAGGCUGGCUGAGGGUCUGCAGCCAGCUUCCGGUCAGACCCCAGGUCCUCCAGCGGCUGCGGCCUUCAGCGUCAUCUCCACGGCAGCCCCUGUGUACUGGGGGCUGGGGGGCCUGGCGAGGCCCCUCGAAGUGGUACAGCUUGCACUCUGGGGACCCAAAGUCCCCCCACCGGGCCCAGGCGGAAGCACCAGGCAUUUCUGGUCCCAGCCGAGGUCUGAGGCAAAGUCGAGUGCUGGCCGUCCGCACGGCCCCGCGGUGUCUCACCUGCCUGAAAGGGAGGAAGGAAGCCUGUGGAGCCCCAUCCGUUCUCCCGCGGCGCAUCCUCCAGGAGAGGGUGGGGAAGGAGGAGACAUCCUGGCAGACACCCCCCCACGUCCCCCACCUCCCAGCUCUGAGCUGAGGAGGCCCUGGAAGAGGGCCAUGGCUACUCCGAGGGAGGGCCGGGGUAGGGUUCUCCUGUCCAGGGGACACUGCUGGCCCAGCCCCACCCAAGCAGGGGAAAUCUGCCCUGGGAGCCACUGUCCCUCAGGACGCCCCCUGCAACCAGCCACCUCUCGUCUGGGCCUCACCAAGACCCCAAGACUCAAGAGCUCCUGUCUCACCAGUGGGACCCUCCAGUCCUGCUGGGGGUGUGUCCUGGGUCCUGGAGUCUGGGCCCCUCACUGGGUAGGGUAUAUGGGUAACAGGCCCAGUGUGGUCCCACUGGACAGGGCCUCAACCAACCAUCUCCCACUCCCAUGCCUCUUCCUCCAAGAAGCCCAGGUGGCGUGGGUGCUUCGAGUCUCUCUCGAAUUCCUGUCUUCUGUCCCCUUUCAAGCCACUGUGUCCUUGUAAGUUCCACCCCAUGGUCCUUCCCAUCCCUGCUGGUCAGUCCCUGGGAUACAUGUCCUGUUACUCCAGACACCUAUCCGCCUCCAGCGCGGAGGCCAAGGCGAAACCACGGUCUGGACGUGUUUUUUUGGUGCCACCGCCAGCCCCUGGGGUUCUCUUGGGCCUGGCUGCUGGGACCCCAGCACCCAGAGUCACGGCAGUGGUGGGCAUGGGGAGGGCCUAGCCUGGUACCUCCCUGCUCGGCUCCCGCGGCUGGGGGUCGGAGAGGGGUGGAGAGCGUGGGCCGCACAGCCUCGGCCGGGAGAGGGAGACUGGAGUGUGUGUGUGUGCGUGCCUGCGCGUGCGUGCCUCGGUCGUAUCUCGGCUGGUGCUGCGUGUCCCUGCGUGUCGGGGUCCGCUCGU